AGGGCCUGAAACAAUGUCCUCCACCGAGAGAAACGUAAAGGACACUUGAUCACACAAUCCCUGGAAUAAUAUCCAGGAAACACUUGCUGGAGCCACUCGCAGCACCCUUCCCUGGCAGCACACUUGGGGACAGCGAGGAGAUGAGCGCAUCUCUGAAUUACAAAUCUUUUUCCAAAGAGCAGCAGACCAUGGAUAACUUAGAGAAGCAACUCAUCUGUCCCAUCUGCUUAGAGAUGUUCACGAAACCUGUGGUGAUUCUCCCUUGUCAGCACAACCUGUGUAGGAAAUGUGCCAGUGAUAUUUUCCAGGCCUCUAACCCGUAUUUGCCCACAAGAGGAGGUACCACCAUGGCAUCAGGGGGCCGAUUCCGCUGCCCAUCCUGUAGACAUGAAGUGGUUUUGGAUAGACAUGGGGUAUAUGGACUUCAGAGGAACCUGCUGGUGGAAAAUAUCAUUGACAUCUACAAGCAGGAGUCCACCAGGCCAGAAAAGAAAUCCGACCAGCCCAUGUGCGAGGAACAUGAAGAGGAGCGCAUCAACAUCUACUGUCUGAACUGCGAAGUACCCACCUGCUCUCUGUGCAAGGUGUUUGGUGCACACAAAGACUGCCAGGUGGCUCCCCUCACUCAUGUGUUCCAGAGACAGAAGUCUGAGCUCAGUGAUGGCAUCGCCAUCCUCGUGGGCAGCAACGAUCGAGUCCAGGGAGUGAUCAGCCAGCUGGAAGACACCUGCAAAACUAUCGAGGAAUGUUGCAGAAAACAGAAACAAGAGCUUUGUGAGAAGUUUGAUUACCUGUAUGGCAUUUUGGAGGAGAGGAAGAAUGAAAUGACCCAAGUCAUUACCCGAACCCAAGAGGAGAAACUGGAACAUGUCCGUGCUCUGAUCAAAAAGUAUUCUGAUCAUUUGGAGAACGUCUCAAAGUUGGUUGAGUCAGGAAUUCAGUUUAUGGAUGAGCCAGAAAUGGCAGUGUUUCUGCAGAAUGCCAAAACCCUGCUAAAAAAAAUCUCGGAAGCAUCAAAGGCAUUUCAGAUGGAGAAAAUAGAACAUGGCUAUGAGAACAUGAACCACUUCACAGUCAACCUCAAUAGAGAAGAAAAGAUAAUACGUGAAAUUGACUUUUACAGAGAAGAUGAAGAUGAAGAAGAAGAAGAAGGCGGAGAAGGAGAAAAAGAAGGAGAAGGAGAAGUGGGAGGAGAAGCAGUAGAAGUGGAAGAGGUAGAAAAUGUUCAAACAGAGUUUCCAGGAGAAGAUGAAAACCCAGAAAAAGCUUCAGAGCUCUCUCAGGUGGAGCUGCAGGCUGCCCCUGGGGCACUUCCAGUUUCCUCUCCAGAGCCACCUCCAGCCCUGCCACCUGCUGCGGAUGCCCCUGUGACACAGGGGGAGGUUGUACCCACUGGCUCUGAGCAGACCACAGAGUCUGAAACUCCAGUCCCUGCAGCAGCAGAAACUGCGGAUCCCUUGUUUUACCCUAGUUGGUAUAAAGGCCAAACCCGGAAAGCCACCACCAACCCACCUUGCACCCCAGGGAGCGAAGGUCUGGGGCAAAUAGGGCCUCCAGGUUCUGAGGAUUCGAAUGUACGGAAGGCAGAAGUGGCAGCAGCCGCAGCGAGUGAGAGGGCAGCUGUGAGUGGUAAGGAAACUAGUGCACCUGCAGCUACUUCUCAGGAGUUAGUAAUCUGCCUAGCGCUUUUGGCUUUUCUUAUUCUUCACUACAUCUGGAGUCAGAUUCAGUGCUUGAUUUUUACUUUAAUGGAUUGGAUUUGAGGCUCCUCCCCUCCAGGGACAGGCUGCAGCUCCAGCGAGUGGCAGUGGAGCUGAUUCUGAGCCAGCUCGCCAUAUCUUCUCCUUUUCCUGGUUGAACUCCCUAAAUGAAUGAUAUUCAUUCCAACUGCUGCCCCUCUGUCUGCCUGGCUGAGAUGCAUGUGGGCAGCAGGAAGCCCAAGUGAAAUUAAUAUUAUGCAGAUGAUGAAAGGGACCUCUGAACAGGAUUUCUGCAAAAAUAGCCCCAAACUGCAAUUCCAUAUGACUUAUCUAACAUCUUGGGGGGAAAGAAUAUUUUGAGAAAAUAGUUGCAGAAAGCACUGGAAAUAAUAAACUUGAUCUUAUACAAAUCUUCUAUUGUGUGGAAAAUGUUGUGAAGGGUGUGUAGGUGUGGUACAUGUGUAUGUCACUAACAAGUGGCAAAUGGUGAAAAAAGUGGUCACUAUGCUUUUGUCUCUCAUAGGCACUGACUUUUUGUUAUUAUAUUAUGGUAGCUUUCAUUUCCUUUACUCUUUAACAGUGCAGGUGGUCAGUGAAAAUCAGUGUCAACUCAGAAGUGACUGAUUUAUCAAUACAUGGACAAAAAGUAAAUCAUUGACCAAAGCUAUGAAAUGUUUCACAAAGUUUUCCUCUUUUGCAUAACAGAUGUCACUGGAUGUACAUUCAGAAAUGUUCUUUGAAUUUGGUGACACUUUCAUGGUCCAGAAAGCUGAAGGCCUGGGCAUCUCUUGUGACAUUUUUCUAAUAUUAGUUUUAGAUUUUCACGUAUUAGGCACUUUAGUUGAAUCUUCCAGCAAAAGCUGUCUACUUUCUCUUUUAUUCACUGUGGCACCAAUCUGGUAAAUUGUAGAACAAUUGCAUGUGUUUAAAUAUAUAUACAAACAUAUCACACAUUAAAUAUAUAUAUAUUUAAAUCAUGCUUUGUUAAUAUUUGUCCCACCAUAAUGCCUCCUUCAGAACAUAAGUGUAACUUUAUAUGAACUCUUAAAUAAAUGAUGUUUUUAAAA